AAAGAAAGUCUUUUGCCCUGUAACUGACUUUGACCAAUUUUCCUUCUCUAUAUUUGUUAAAUUAACUUUGGCGUUUUUCAUCUUGGCUUACUAAUUUCUGACUACCUCUUCCAUCCUAUCUAUUCGUUGCAGUGUGGAAGAUAAACGUGAGCUUACCCGUGACUCCUGGGCCUUGGCAUCUGUCUUUUGCAGACUGCCUGGAUUGCUAUCCAAUGUAUUAGUCUGUCAAGGUUUAAAUUUGGUGUAGGUGGGAGGGAUGUAGGGACGGACACACAAGCUUUUAGAAAAGCCAGGCUCUCUAAGGAAUUCAAGUGAAGCAGAGACUUCUUUUCAUAUUAAAGCAAUGUAAAAUGACAGAAAGAAUUAUAGGUAUAAAAUUGUGUAUUACAAAUGGGAAAUUUAAUUGGACCAGAGUACAUAGCAGGUGAUAUUGAACCCCCUACCCUGAAAGAGCCUUUGUUUUUCAAGUAUGGGAUAGAACUGGAACACAGGGGCCUUUGUACAUGGACACUGUAUAGGCAUCAUUUGUUUUACUAAACACUCCUUUCUAAAGACGGCAAAAGCAUAUUGGCAGCAAGGUAGACUUGUCAGAACAAUAUACAUGACUUUUAGACCCAAGCAGGUGGACUGCUUGACAUGAUUCCUCCGGGUGCAACGAAUUUUUGUGUGUGGGCAGAAAGGAAUGAGUCUUAAUACUUCUCAGCAAUAUACUGUGGUUUAUUUUCCUCUCACAAAGAAAAAGAAUCAUUUCAAAGAAAUAACAAUUAUAAAGUACAGCAGCUUGUAAACGUUCUCCAUUCUUUUUAAUUCCCAGGAAUGUGUGAUGGGGCAGGAGAUUUGGUCCCUGUGGAGUGUCUGUAUAGCCAAAGGUUCUUCACAGAUUUUGGUUCUGCCUCCUUUGCAAAAGUAGAAGAAUGCCUUUCCUAUGUUGUUAAAAAGAUAUUUAAAAAUUAAUAUUUUGCACAGUGCUUUUCAUUAUGGGGCCAUUUUUGUCUUAACAUGGAGGCAAAAAACCUGUGACUUCCUCCCUGAAGUUCCUUCUACCCUUACAUGGCUGAAUCUGGGAGAGGUUCGUGCAUUUUUCCCAUCCUUAUGGAAGUACACAAGUAAUUACAUGAACGUGCUACCUGUGCAUACUUUUAUUGGCUUUUGAAACAUUUUAUAGCUUUUCUAUGUGUCACAUGCCAUGAUAUGUAUAUUACAUUGAUUAUUUAAUAUUUACUACAUAUCCACGAGGUUUACUCUUAAGAUAUUUUGGCUCAGAGAGAUAAUUUUGUCAAGGUCUCAUAGUGACUAAGUUGCAGGACAGACCCAAGCAGUCUGGUUUCAUAGCACAGCUUCCUAACCACCGCACUGUUUUGCGUUUUGUCUGUUUAAAGGAGUAUGCAUAGAGAAGAAUAUUGGAGUACCUUGCUUAAAAAUGACCAAAGGACAGAUAACCCUAAAUAUAAAAGAGCAAAGGAGUUGAAUAGACCUUUCUCCAAAGAAGAUAUACAAAUGGCCGACAAGCACGUGAAAAGAUGCUCCUCAUCAUCAGUUAUUAAGGAAAUGCAAAUCAAAACCACAAUGAGGCUGGGCGUGGUGGCUCACGCCUGUAAUCCCAGCACUUUGGGAGGCCAAGGUGGGAAGAUCACCUGAGGUCAGGAGUUUGAGACCAGCCUGGCCAACGUGGAGAAACCCUGUCUCUCCUAAAAAUACAAAAAUUAGCCAGGCCUGGUGGGGUGUGCCUAUAAUCCCAGCUACUCGGGAGGUCGAGGCAGGAGAAUCGCUUGAACCCGGGAGGCAGAGGUUGCCGUGAGCUGAGAUCAUGCCACUGCACUCCAGCCUGGGCCACAGAGCGAGACUCCGUCUUCAAAAAAAAAAAAAAAGAAAAAAAAACCGUAAUGAGGUGCCACUUCACAUUUACUAUUAAAUGUAAUAGAAUGAAAUGUAGUAGGAUGGCCGUGAUCAGUAAAAUGGAAAAUAGUAAGGAUGUGAAGAAACUGGAACCCUGUACAUUGCUGAUAGGAAUGUACAGUGUGGUAGCCACUGUGGAAUCCACUUCCUUAAAAAGUUGAUGUAUGACCCAGGAAUUCCACUGCCAUAUACACACACAAAAGAAUGGAAAACUGAUACUUAAUUUCACAUACAUAUAUUAUAAAUAGUAUUAGUAUUUACAAUAGUGAAAAGGUAGCAACAGCCAAAAUGCUCGUUGUUAGUUGAAUGAAUACACCAAUUGUGAUCUAUCCAUACAAUCGAGUAUCAUUCAGCCAUCAAAUGAAUGAAGUACCCAUACAUGCUCCAGCACGGGUGAACCCGGAAUACAUUAUGCUUAAUGAAGGGAGCCAGACACAAGACGCCACAUGCUCUGUGAUUCCGUUUGUAUGAAAUGUUCAAAGUAGAUGAAUCCAUAGAGACGGAGUGCAGAUUGAUGGUCGCUAGGGCUUGUGGGAAGGGGCACCCGAGAGCAGCUGCCUUCAGUGGGUAUCGAGUUUUCCUCUGUAGUGAUACAAAUGUUUUGGAGCUGGAUAGGUUGGUGGUCGUUUAUCAUUGUGAAUGCACUCAAUGUUACUGAAUUGUUCUUAAAAUAGUUAAUUUUAUGUUUCACCUCAAGAAAAAACAAUAAUGACUAAGUUAUCCCGCGGCCCCUAGCUCUCAGGUAUUACAGUCAGUUGCAGCUUUUAUGGAGCACAUAUUUGCAUGUUAUUGGGCCAAUAGCAAGUUAAACAAACACUGUGAUAGGCAAACAUUAUCUUGAGCACUUUACAUGUGUGGACAAGCACAAUGACUGACGUGGUUCCCAGACUCCAGCCGAGACUCCAGGAACCAACAGCCUUUAAGAAUUAACAGGGGAACAGACAAAAUAUGAAGGCUGUAUGUUGAUUUAGCAGACACUCAGCAAAUAAAGGGCUUACAUUUUGGUGACGCCAACAGCUAAAAUGCUUUUUCACACAGUGAGUAGGGUGUUACCAGACUUACAUGUGUGCUCAGGCAGCAUGAUCUUAUCCUCCUCCUAAUCAGGGUAGGUUUCAGUCAUGCAUGCUGGAGCAAAUGAUUCCGGUGAGAGAAUCUGAAAGAACCCUAUACAAACAUGUACCUUUUUUUCUUUAGGACUGUGAAGGGAACGUGGCAGUGUGUGGCCUGGUGCAGCCUGUGCCCAGAGGGUUUUUCACGUUCAGUAUAGACCUUUGAUGUUCUCAGGUUAUUUUCCAAGUUGCCCAGAAGCAUGACACAUACACUGCACUAAAUCCUUGAGGAGUUGCAAGAAAACAGAUAGUGCUUUUCUUCUUCUUUUUUUUUUAAAAAAGGGAGGGGAACCUAGUCCACAGUGCAGCAAAGCAGUUUGUCUGGUGUAGGUAAUGGGGGUGUGGGUCACCGAGGAUGACCCUUGUUGACCUACAUUCCUGAUCUCUCCCAUUCAGAUGUGCACAUGUAGAUCCAUUUACUUCUAGACAGCCCUCUUAGGUUACUGAAAUUAUUGAUUCAGCAUUGUCUGCAUUGCCAGGGCCUCCUCUCACCCUAAUGUAGAGUGGGAAGUGGACAUUUUUACUUAAAAAUGUGUGAAUUUUUCUUACCCAAAUAUUACUUUAUUGUCUCAUUGUAAAAAUUUCAUAUAUCUAUAUAACAGAUAUAUAUAUCUGUAAGUAACUUUAAUAAUCAGACAAGCCACCUUCUCCACUCCCCGACCUUUAUUCACUUUUACCAUUUGCAUCUAAGCUCACCUUAAAAACCUGUGACUGGUACAUGGUGGCCUCUUCAGCUGCACACAAUCUUGCCUGGGAGUUUUCCUGGCCUGAGGCUAUAAGGUGGAAGAUUGUUUCGACGACUUUUAACCCUUCACCUCUCCUCACCCCUGAAAGCAUCAGCAAACCUCCCUCUUUCUGUCCCGAAAUCCCCAAAGGCAAGGAUGUCUUUUCCUGUUUUCUAGAGCUCACUCUUUUAUUAUUUGAUGGACCUCACUCUACUAGUUAUCUAGUCUCAAUUAUUUUCACCUUUUUUAGCCUUUAAAUGUGCCUGUCUUCCUCUUAGGAAGGAAGAAAGCGAGGGAGGGGAAAAAAAGAAGUAAUGCCUUUGCUCCACCUCUUCCUCUACUUAUCUUUGAAUCAUCUCUCCUUUCACAAUUACAACUGAAAUUAUUUACAUUUUUAGUCUUCACUUUCUUACUUCUUGUCACCUCCGCUGUAGUCUGGCGUUCAGGUCCUUAACUCAAUUGAAACUGCUGUAGUUGCGAUGAGCAGCAAUCUCCAUGUUGCUCAAUCCUCCGGAUACUCUAACUUCAUGUGUCCUGUGGACCGCUCCCUUUCGGGAACGCUUUUCCCUGGGCUUCGGUGACACCAUACUCUCCUAGUUUUCUUCCUGCACUACUGUCUUCCCAGUCGGUGGGGUUCUUUCGCCACCUUGUUUGUUCUCUGCACACUGUCUGUGGGUUACCUUACUGAUUCCUGUAGCUUCAUUCACCGUCUCUGUGUGGCUGACUCCCAAAGUUAGCUUGUGUUUUAGUUACCUUUGUAUACUUCCAGCAGCCAACAUGGGACCUGUUGCACAACAGUAGCCUAUGUUAAGUAAAUGAACGGACUGAUAAAUAGAUGUUUUCCAUGAUUGAUACUCUUCCCAAAAUCUUUCAUUAUUACCAUUUGUCACCCAUCACAAGAACAUAAACUCCAUGAGAGCAGAGACGUUAUCAGUCUUGUUCAGGACUGUGUGCCUGGCACGUGGCACACGUAUCCAGUAUGAGCAAAAAACAAGUGGCUCACCCAAAAUGAUCCUGGCACCAGGAAGUUUCUCUUUGGGCCUGGCUUCCUUGGUUACUCACAUGCCCCCGUCCAUGUGUUGUAGGAAGAGGAAAGAUGUAAGCAUUAAGGAUUUGGCUCACUGGGGCUGGUCCUGGUGGUUUGGAAAUAGCAGAUCUCUAAGGCAUUCCAUCACCUCAUGAGAGAAGUCUUAUUUAUUUAUUUAUUUAUCUAUUUAUUUAUUUAUUUCUUGAGACGGAGUCUCGCUCUGUCGCCCAGGCUGGAGUGCAGUGGCAUGAUCGCAGCUCACUGCAACCUCCGCCUCCCGGGUUCAAGUGAUUCUCCUGCCUCAGCCUCCUGAGUAGCUGGGACAGGCACCCGCCACCACGCCCAGCUAAUUUUUUUGUAUUUUUAGUAGAGACAGGGUUUCACCAUAUUGGCCAGUCUGGUCUGGAACUCCUGACCUCAGGCAAUCUGCCUGCCUUGGCCUCCCAAGAAGCCUUAUUUUUAUAUAGCUCGUUUUCUCUCACCUGGGAUCCCAGGUCAACCCCUUUUCAAGUUGGGAGAAACCAGCUAAACAUUUUGUGUUUUAAUUUAAAUUUUGUGGUCUGAGUUGACUCUUGCUAGGGUGGGGGUAGAGGAGGAAACCCAGCAGAGAACUUGAACUAAGUCAAAAUGGCACCUUCCCUCCUGAAUAUUCCUUUUAUUAAGAUGUCUGCAGAUCUCCGAGCAUUAGGUCUUCCAUUCUUGGAGAUUCUGACUUUCCUCUGUCAUUAUUUCUCUGCGGAAGGUUCUAACAUUUGGCCAGUUGUGAUUUCUCUGAGCCCUUUGCAACACUGCAGGGAGCACACUCAGUUGUAUGCAGUGGGGCUGAUAGCAUCCAGGUCUCAGAAGCACUUUCCUUCCAUAUCAUUGCCGAUUUCCUGUUUCUUUUUUAAUUGCACUUGUUCCUUUUAUAAAGUGACAGUAGCUAAAUUUAUUUCUCAAGAUGCUUACAUGCUCUUUUAAAGAGUAUCUAAAUUAAUAAACAUUGAGUACAGAAACCUAAUCUGAAUUUGUGUUUUUAUUGAGAGCACUCUCAUUAAACACAGGCUGGAAAAAAAAAGAAUCAACCAGACCCUGAUGCCUCUUGCAAAAUCUGAUCUGUUCCAAGUCUAGCAGGUAGAGUCCUGAUUGCCUUUAUUUGCAAGUUCAGAAGAAUGCAGGUAGGUGAAGAUUAGAAUGGCCUCGUAGUGAAUAUGUAUAAGCCUAUAAAAUUAAAGUAGAACUUGGUUAAAGAGCAAUACAAUCUCUUGCUAUUUCAUGAAUGCUUAGCAGUGUUAUAAAGACGUGAACAUAUUGCUGUGUUUCAGUGAGCUACAGCCUUACCCUUUGAUAUGCUUAAUUAUUUUCAAGGUCAUUUCUUUUUAUAAAAUCAAGGCAAGCUGGAAAAUGUCAAACAGCCUACAAGUAUAGAAUAAACUAUUUUCAUUGUCAUUUUAUAGUCAUAUAUAGUUGUGGUUUUGAGUUUCCCAGUUACAACCAGUCACUGAGUGUAAGAGUCACAAUAAAUUCUCUUAGGAACAUGGUAUCCUUUAUCUCUUCAACCAUUAAUGUUCCAAGGAUAUUUUCAAAUGAAAGAAUGAUAAAAAUUAGUUGAUGCGUUCUGGGAAUAUGCACAUUUAAAAUUUCAAGUUAACAAUACAGAUGAAGGUGGUUAAAUGUGCAAGAGCUAGCUACAAUAAGAGAAAUGUAGUUGAGGCUACUGCUGAAGGGAUUAUGUACUUAGCCUCUAAGCCACUUAGGAUAUAUAUUAAGUUGGUUGUGCUCUACCAUUUUGGCUGAAGAUAAUUUUCCCUUACAUAAAGCAAAUAUUUAGUAACAAGUGAGGUAAGUCUGAGUUGUUCAUUAUGCAGGUUAUAUGGUACGGUUGAAAUCCUGACCAUACCACUAGUCUCUGUACCUCUGAGUAACCCUCACAUUGUAUUGUACUUAAAGGUUUGAGGUGAUUCUUAAGUAGGCAUUGUAACUGAGAAAUAUAAGUUUCAGAUUUUUGCUGCCACCAGCUGUUAGGAAGUGCUGGUUAUUUUGUAAUGAUGCCUGAAAACCAUGGACUCCUCAGCAUUGUGAAAUUUGGAUUUAGGGGUAACACAAACAAAAAUUCCAGAUUCUUGAGGAGAUAAGAAUUUUAAAUGAUUCAAGAACAUGCACACCAAUUCUAUUAGUUUAAAAAUAAUUAAUAUGCCUUACGUGGCAGUAGAGUUCAGAUCAGUUGGCUGCAAUCUUCAGAAAUAUUUAUUUAUAUGGUGUCAACUUAGGUUGUCUCUGAGACACAUUCCAAUUGAUACUUCUGCCUGCCUCUGACAGACUUCUUUUCCCAGAAACACCCUCCACAUAUGCUUAUUCCUGUUAGCUUAACCUAGUUCUAGAAUGUUCUUUUAGGGUAAUUGAGGUAAGACUCUCUUUUCACUUAGCCAACUUGGAGUUGUUGGCAUUUCAAUUAGUGGUCAUUGCGGGAUAGCAUUACUUCACUCAUUCUCACUUUAGAUACAUUGCUCCCACCGACUUAUGUUGUAUAGUAGUCCUUCUCUGAUAGAUUCACCAAGAAACUACUGUUGCUUAGCCGGCCAGGUACACGUCCACACGCUUUGACCUCACUUACUGAACCCACAGCUCUGCCACGCUGUCCUCUUCUGUUCCUGAAACUCUCCAAGCUUGCACCCAGGCUGUUAUCUUUGUAAUAUUUUUUUUACCCUCUUGCAACCAACACACAUGCACUAUUGCCUGGCAAACUCCUACUUCUAGGAGUUUUUGGCUUGAAGCCUGCUAUUGGCUUAACUAGAGAAGAGUCAUAUGAAGGUCUGGAGAGAGGCCAGAUAAGUCAGAGCUGUGCAUUCAAAGAAAAAUCAGGACUUGGGAAGACAUGUUCCUGCCUGUCAUUUGAAAUAUACUGUCAUUGGCCAGACCUGUAUUUGAUUCUCUUUUUACAUUUUAGAAGAACAAUACUUUUAAGCCAUACAUUUGAUAAGAAUGAUCAAACCACCACUUUGUUGCAGGUUUACUGCUAGGCUCUGUGGGUACAUCUAUUCGCGGAGAAAGAAAAGUAAAUUAAUAAUUACAAUAGAGCAUGAUAUACCAAGGUGGAGGCAUAGACGGGGGCUGGGGAACAUGAAGGAGACCAUCGAAAUCAAAGGUGGAGGCCAGAGAAGGCUUCCUGGAGAAACGAGGCCUGAAUUGCUUUCUGAAGAACUGGUAAAAGAUAAUCUGAUGAAAACGGGUUCAGCCUGGAAGAGAGGAUGCCUGAAAUGGAGGGAACAGCCUGUGUAAAGAUGGAAACAAUCUAACAGCUUAGCACACAGAGAAAACUGUAAGUCACUCAGUCCUCAGUGAGUUUGAAGUGCACGCUGAAAGCUGUAGGGCCCCGGAGAAGAAGCCUCUUGGGAAAAUAGGCCUUUACAACCACAGCAAAGACAGUCUGUCAUGCUUGGCGGCAUGCAGGUGAGCUGUGCCAGGUGUGCCAGGCAGGCUGCAUGUUCAUUUGUAGAGGACUCUGCAAAUGAGGCGCAGGGUGGAGCGGGGUGGUGCUGCCAGUGAACAAAGAGAAUGAGGCUUACCUAGAGCAAUCGCUGGAACACCUGUCUUGUCUGAUGGCAUCGUCUCGCUUGUCUGAUGGCGUUGUCUCACAGUCCCAGCCUGCAUGUUGGUAAUGUUCAGGGCGAGAGGAGUAAGCAAACAGCCCCAGCUUCUGUCUGCUGCUGCUCUGGAGAAUAUCAGAGUUGCUCUGCCAGGUCCCACAGGUUCUUUUACAUUCACCAUCUCUAUUUAAUCUUCCCAGAUUUGAAAAUAAUGGUUUAUCCUGGAUGUGAUCUGAAAGUAUUUCCCCAAUGCUUACCCACAGGAGUCACCCACAGAAUCCUCACUCACUGCUGUCCCCCAUGUGAGAGCUUGCUAUAGCUCUGUGUCAGGAAUUUGGGAACAGUGUUGCUGGUAAUGUGGAAAUCAUGAGAGACGUCAUGUGGGGUUAGACAGCAGCCACCUUCAUAGCUCCCUGCCUUUCUCACUUCUCCUAGACCUCUUGAUUCUCUGAUUCCUCGGGAAACUCAAUUACCUUUCCUUGAUUAUGCAGAGCAAUUUAACUCUCAAACAUCCUUCGGCUCUGGGCCCACCUUUGCACAUUCAGAAGCUCAUUAAUGUUUCAGCACCGAGGAACUGGCAGGAGCUUUGACAUUUCAGUGUUGUCUUUUCUCCCUCCCCAGGUAUCUCAGAGUGAGAAGGAGCAGUAUAGAGAUCUGCUUUCCCACUAAUAUGAAUUUUCACCCCAAACCUCAGCAUCAGAUGAAGAUAGUCAUUUUCAGUUUUAAUAUUUUUUUCUUCUAUGCAUAUUAGGUAGGCAAAGAAAGACAUAGAGUUCUCUCUAUCUAGAACUUUGAAAUAAAUGAAAAUAUUAGAACAAAUAAACACUUCCUAUAAAUGUGAGUGAAUAGGACAGUAGGUAAUAACCGGAAUGGAUUUGGAAGAAUGGAUUCUGUCAGCUCAUACUCAGAGGCAUAUUGUUAAAGCAGGGAUAUGAAGACAGCAGCAGAGUACAGGGGUUACAGGCAUGAAUUUAGGAGUCAGAUCAAGCUGGGUUAUAAUUGUGUCUCCUCUCAUUCCUAAUCUGUGAAUUUAGCUGAGUCAACUUAACCUACUGAGUUUACUUCAUUAUUUGUAAAAUAAAGGUAAUAUCACCAGGUAAAGUGGUGCACUCCUGUAAUCCCAGCUCCUCAGGAGGCUGAGGCAGGAAGAUCUCUUGGGCCUAGUAGUUGAAGACCAGCCUGGGCAGCAUAGCAAGACCACAUCUGGGAGGUGGUGUGGAGAAAAAAAAAAGUACUCCCCCCACUCCAGGACCUGGCGAGCCCUCAGUACCGGUGGCUCCCAUUUCACUCACAGUCUUCCUGGGCUGUGCUUCCGUCGUGUUCCCUGCACUCCUACACCCUGGUCUUCUGUUUUACAAGCUGGACCUAUUAUCCCACAAGGGACUUCGCACUUGCCAUGGCCCUGCCUAGGAUGCUUCAGCAGACAUGGCUUAUCACAGGCCAGUGCCCAUUCUUGCUUUCUUCCUGCUAACAGAGUUUCAAUUUUUUUUUUUUUCGGGGCUACAAAAGGCCCAUUCAUGCCAGUUAAAAGCAAGAAACUUCCUUAGCUUUACUGUAUCUGUGGGACAGUUUAGAGCAGAUGUAAGUGAACACUUAUGGGCAGGGCUUCUGGGGAAGGUACUAUUUGCGGAUAGGAAGGGACUGACUAGGCUGGCUAGACACACCCUGCCCUUCAGCCUUCCCCAUUCUUCAUCACUGGAAGGCUGAGUUACUGCUCAGUAGUAGAGCAGCCCCCGGUGAGCUACACACCAGGAGGGGCAAAGAAAAAGGUAUAAGGAGCUUGGCUCCCUAAUGGCAUUGUGGGAAUCCAGUGAGAAAAGGGACCCUUUCUGUGGGUAAAUCAUUUUAUUUGGUAUUCUGUUGAAAGCAGUGAAUUUAACUCCGGCUAUUACACGUGCUUUCCCCCCAGCACUUUAGAAAAACCUUUUUUAAUGGUUGGCGCUCUCAUUCUUCAGGACUCCAUUGAAUGUGACUGCCUCAAAGAUGCCUUCCUUGGUCAUUCCCUCUAAAGUAGCUCUUCUUCCACACGCUCGUGGUGUAUUCUGUUUUAUUGUCGCCACAUCAUGAACAUUAUCUGAAAAUAUCUUCUCAUUUAUUUACUUCUCGGUACUGCAUAUCUCACGCUGGGUAGAAUUAAGCUCCAUUGGAAUAAGGACCUGGUGUAUCUUGUUCAUUGCUCUAUCUGUACUGAGAACUAUGCUGAUGUAAAGCAGGUGCUCAGUAAAUGUUUCUUAAAUGCAUACAAAACGUGUUAUCUAGAUUAAAGAGCAACUUUUUACAUUUAAUCAGUAGUUUGUCAAGGAGAGGAAAAUUAAGGUGGAAUUCAUGGUGUUGGAGUGAUUAUAUCCCUUUAUAUUUAUAUAUUCUGGUUUGUCUGUAUAUUUAUGUGUAAAUAUAAUUCACAUCAAUAAAUUGAGCACGUAUUAUGUGCUAGGAAUUCUAAGCACCUUCUACCUUUUCAUAUUUUUCAAUCAAUAGUUUUAUAAAAAAGAGUAAAUAUAAAAAGGUAUGCUUUACUCUACGGGGUAGUUCUCAAAAAAACAAAGCCAAUUUCCUCUUUUAAUCAUUGCGUAUUUAUUUAUUUAUCUGAAAGUGUUUCUUCAAAGUGAAAGUUGAAAUGUGUAGUAAACUUUCAAAUAGAACUGCAUUUUGUCUCAGUAGAAAAUUCUCCAUCACAUAUAUCUCAAUGACUUUGUGUCAAAACCUACUAUUUUACCUGUCAAGAUGAUCUUCUUCCCUUACUGUGCAUUUCAGAGGAUGGAAGUACAUAGAAUGAAAUUUUAGUGUCAGAUACAUCAAUUACAAACCAACGGAGCUGUUUCAUUUUGCACCAAUGAUGGAGAAAGAGAGUCAGGGGAAGAAUGAGUCUAUUUUUACCUUAAAGUAGCAGCAUUCAGGAUAAGAUGUCUUCACUUAGAAAUCAGUCAUACCCUCGACUGUGGAUCAGUGCAGGCUUUAAUAAUUCAUUCUGAAACCUGUGCUUCCCCAGCUAGUGCUCCCUGGCUCUUUACUUAUUUAAAGGUCUGUUUACCUCUCAGUUUGCACCUGCAACUGUCCAUUCAAUCUGCUGUGCAUAACCAGUGGGGAAUAAGCCCAUUAAUUAGAAUAAUUUAAGCAUCUCAGCUUCCUGCAAUCUUCAACCUAGUGGGGUCUCACUGGCAACAUACUUCUUUAUGAAGCUCAUCUCUCAUCUGAACCACAGGUCUAGAUCCUUAAUGCAGUGAUCAGAAGCUUGCGAUUCUGUGGCACUUGAAAAUUUGGAAGCCCCAUAAUAUAUGGUCUGGUUUGCAGAUUCUCAACGCAGUUCCACUAGGGAUUGACACACCCAUGCUAGUCUCUUGUGUAAUUAACCACAACAACAGAUUGUAGCAGAAUAUAAAAGAAGGAAGCUGACCUAUGGGGGGGAAAAAAGACAAAGCUUAUUGUUGUGGCAAGGAGGGACUUCAUUCUUUUAGGACAGGCUAUCCAGGUGACCUGAUAAUGGAUAUAGAGGAAUUCCAGUAUUGAAUUAGGCCUUUUGCAUCUGACAAAGGACAGGAUUAAAAGGAAUAACUUGGGAGGGAAUGUCUGUUGGCAUCUGUUUGCUUGAUGAUCCACCCAUGAUGCCUGACCGGAUGAGAGCCUGUCUUUGGGAAGCUCAUGAGUUUAUAAGAAACAGAAUUGCUGCUGUUUCUUAAACUAGGCAGUGUUCUGGUGAAGAACGUGGGCUCUGGGACAAGAGGGCCAUUUGCUGGUUGUUUUCUCUUGUCGAGUUAAUUAUCGCUCUGCCUCAGUGUUCUCAUCUAUAAACUGUGAGUAGCCAGACCUCCCUGAAGGACACUUGCUGGCAAGGCCAAAACACAAGCUACAAACAGAGGCCAAGCAGUGGAGGCAGGGGGCGCCCCGAAGGGACAGGUGACAGGCAGUGAUGCCAAGGGCAGCUCUUGUCCUCGUCCCAGACUUCGCUACUCAUUGGCUUUGGUGAUGUAAGCGCUAAGUAAAAAGCUACUGCUGUUCCAAACAGAUGUGAGGCGAAGGUUUAAGCUUUGCGGUCUGCGUAUGACCUUUUCAUCUUUGCCCUCGUACCUCCUAGCAUCCCUUUCUUUGUGAAUGGUGCCUACGUUGGAUUGUUUAUCCAAACCAGACACCUGAGUCAUUCUAGGGUCCUUUGUGUCACCCACCUCCAUGAUUCAGCAAAUCACUAAAUACGGUUUGUUCGACCUUUUUACCUGUGAUUUCCUUUUUAGUGUAGGUAAUUCCUCAUCAGCCUUCAAAUUCAGCUCAAAUAUGACCUCUUAAGGGAAAGCAUUCUGUGACUCUCCCUUUCGUAGUCUGAUUAAGGUGCCCGUUUUCUUUGCUCCCCAAAACACCUUGUAGAUAUUUUAGGAAACACAGCAUUUCUUGCAAAUGUUAAUUUAGUUUCCUCCACUAGACUCUUAAGCUCCUGUGGGCAGAGACUGAGUCCUAUUUGGUUUUAUAUCCCUAAUGGUUGGCAUAGUGCCUCACAAAUAACAGGCUUUUAAUGUUUAUUGAAGGAACCAAAGAAAGUAGGUUUCUGUGAGUUCACCUUGGAUCAUAACCAUGAUAUAGAACUUAUUUUUAUGGGGAAAAUAUGUUCUUACCUUCCCAAUAACUCAGAGUUAUAAGCUUUAGAGUAUUAGCAGAUGUCAUUCUAAAAGUUCCUUUCUUUAGAAUCUAAAUUAUUUAAAAAACUUAAUUUUGUGUGCAGGUAAAUUGCUUGUCUCUGCCCUCAUCAACAUCCCAGGGGCAGGAUUUAAAAAAAUCUUCACGUUGUUGUUUUAUUUUGUUUCACUUUUUUCUUGCCCAUUUCUGAUACAAAAAUGGGACAAAGAGCUUUCUGAUGGAAAGUUAUUAUUAGCUCCAUUUACUAGAAAUGAUUCAUAGGCCCAAGGAAGUCUUUUUGCAUGUAGUAAACACAUAGUAACCAAAUUAGGUAUGUGAGCCAAAGGUUAAGAGCCAAAGUCAAACUUCCAGACCUUAACAUUAAUUGAAAAAAAAAAAUUCUGUCCUUCGAACUCUGUAGCUCAAGAUAAAUGUGAUUCUUAGAGGUCGAUAUAUUUUUUUUUUUUUGAAGACAUAGUCUCGCUCUGUCACCCAGGCUGGAGUACAGUGGCACAAUCUUGGCUCAUUGCAACCUCAGCCUCUGAGAUUCAAGCGAUUCUCCUGCCUCAGCCUCUGAGUAGCCAGGACUACAGGUGCGUGCCACCACACUAGGCUAUUUUUUUUUAUUUUUUAUUUUUAGUAGAGAUGGGAUUUUCCCAUAUUGGCCAGGCUGGUCUCGAACUCCUGACCUCAAGUGAUCCACCUGCCUCGGCCUCCCAAAGUGCCGGGAUUACAGGCACGAGCCCCUGUACCUGGCGAGAUGUGUAGUUCUUGGUGCUAACUAUGAGCAUCUUUAGGGCAUGAAGCAGAUCUUCACUUCUGUAUUGCCAGCAUUUAGUACAAUAAGUGUUUGGUGAAAGAUGAACCAAUAAGUGAAUGAUUGUAUUUCCUUUUCAGCUUUCAUGAGAAAUUAUGUGAUGAUCAGACUGUUUGGUUUGAUAACCUUUUAUUGUAAAGGUAGUUUUUGAUUAUUAUAGAGCAGCACUGGUUGAUGGGCUUGAAAUUUUAUAUUUUUCUUUAAUCAGCAUAUCUACAAACAAUCAGUGGAGUAUUCCUUUUGGGUUGCCAUUUUGAAACAAGAAACGUAUGGAAAUAAGGGACGAACAUUAUCUGCUUUCUCUUGGCUGUGUCCUGAAAGAAUUGGAAUUUGCUGUGGAGCAAAAGCUAAAGAUUAAGCAAUAUUUUUUUCUUUUUAAAGUAAUACCAGUAUAAUUGCUGGAAUUAUUAGUAAUAGUAUUACUAUUAUUCAUUAUUAAAUUUCUCAUUUUAUUUCAAUCUCUCCAUCAGGAAUGACUUGUGUAGAGUAAGGGAGUUUGGGAGGGAAGAAAGCUAAUUCAUAAAUUCAUUUUUCUUGUUUAAUAUACUGUUUGUUUUGGGCCAGGCACGGUGGCUCAUGCCUGUAAUCCCAGCACUUUGGGAGGCCGAGGCGGGCAGAUCACAAGGUCAGGAGCUCGAGACCAUCCUGGCUAACACGGUGAAACCCUGUCUCUACUAAAAAUACAAAAAAUUAGCCAGGCGUGGUGGUAGGCGCCUGUAGUCCCAGCUUCUUAUGAAGCUGAGGCAGGAGAAUCACAUGAACCCGGGAGGCGGAGCUUAGAGUGAGCCAAAAUUGCACCAGUGCACUCCAGCCUGGGCGACAGAGUGAGACUCCAUCUCAAAAAAAAAACAAAAAACAAAAAACAAAACAAAAAAAAAACAUUGUUUGUUUUGAUGGUAACUUCAUGUAUUUCAUACAUUGUCAUUGUAACACAUUAACUAAGUGUGGGGAACAAUGAACAAUAAACCAAGAGCUGUUUCUCUGUUGUGAUACUUCUUGUUGCCAAAUUUGUGGGCUUUCAUAGUUCAGGAAAUCUUCCUGCACAACUGCUUUGAAAAUUACUAAAUGUUAAUUACUAUUCUACUGUUUUUAAAGGAAAGCAGAAAACACUGCAUCUGAAAGUCUAUUAAAAGAAACUAGGAGGGCUAUUGGUUUCAAUUUCUAAUAGCUUUAUAGUGUGUCCUGGGCAUCCUUCUGUGCCGUGAGCGGGGGUCAAAUUCUGAAGACUUAAGCCCUGAAGCACUUUGCCGGUAUAAACAGAUCUCUCACUGGGGCAGAUUACUUACCUGGAGCUGUAUGGAGCAGGAUCAGCUAGAACAUUACACCUUUUAUAUCUUACUUUGCCAAAGGUAUCAUUCACUUAGUAAGAGAAAUGUUAACUUUUUCCAUAGUUAGUAGCGAUAGAAGCAGAGCGGAUGGCACAAUGAAGCCAUCGGAGCCUUUAAGGCCCUUAUUAUUUCCAUUGAUUCGUUCAGUGAAUGUAGGCUGCGUGCAAUACCACAUGAGUGGAUAUAGCCAAAGCUAUGCCAGAUUGAUUGAUGGAUUGCCUUUAGUAAACUUGCAGUGUAAUGAGGCCACAGUAAUGUAGAAGAGGGAGUGACUCAUGUAUGGGGCAGUAAGCAGAAAGGAUUAAAGUCUUCUGCACUUUGCAUUUAAGAGGUCAUUAGAACCCACCCAAAGCAAGGGUAGAUUUAGUGCCUAAUGAUGUCACAGUACAUAUUAUGAGAGGUUGGAAAUUUGGGGAAAUGGAGAUGAUAGCAAGUAUAAAGGGUUUUUUUUCUAGCAACCUGGCUAUUAAGGGAUAAAUAAAGUGUUGUAGCUAGAGGUGAAUGAGGUUAAAGGUGGGAUUGUUUAAAAUAGAAGACUUAGGCCAGGAGUGGUGGCUCACACUUGUAAUCCCAGGCUUUGGGAGGCCAAGGCAGGAGGAUUGCUUGAGGCUAGGAGUUUGAGACCAGCUUGGGAAACAUAUUGAUACCCUGUCUGUAUUAAAAAACAAACAAAACAAAACAAAAAAGUAAUUAGCCAGGCAUGGUGGCGCAGCUUCUGGGGAGGCUAAGGCAAGAGGAUUUGUUGAACCCAGGAGUUCAAGGCUGUAGUGAGCUAUGAUCAUACCACUGCACUCCAGCCUGGGUGACAGAGUGAAACCCUGAAAAGCAAUCGGCCAAUCAAAAUAUAAAUAAAAUAUAUUUCCCUCCCUCCCUCCCCCUCUCCCUCCCUCCCUCCCUCCUUCCCUAUCUCCAGCAGGGUUUUAGGCUGAGGGGAAGUGAUGAGUGGGAAGUAAAUGAGACUGAAGAUAAGGAAGUCCAGGUUAUGACUGUAGGAGACAGAGAGGAUGUGGAACACAGGAGAAUGGAUGGUCUGUGUAGGAGGACUGUUCCUCUCAAAAGUGGGGAGAGUUUAAAGGAGAAGGAUAAUGCUGUUUAUGGGGGUUGGGUAGGAAGUUGGUAGCAGGGCUGUGGCUUCUGUUUUCUUUGUGAAUUUGGAAGCAAGAUCAUCUGAGGGAGACGCACACACGCAGAGGCUUGGUGCUUGAGUAGACAGUUGGAAAUUUGAGAGAACUUCUGCACCAUGUGAUACGGUUCUGGGCCCCAUGCAGCUACAAGAGAAAAUUGGACAUCAGAUAUGUUGAGGAAACACUCCCCAGAAUUUGUUGCAUGAUUUCCUCCAUCAAAGCUUAGCAGCCUAGUGUUAUAAAACAUAAAAAUUGCUAACAUUUAUUGAGUGCUUACUUUGUGCCAGGCACCUUACUGUGUAGUAACACAGUCCUCAAAACAGUGUGAAAUAGCUCCUAUCAUUACCUAUUUUUACCAUCCCCAUUUUGCAGAUGUGGCUGAGAAAGGUUAAAUCUGGGUGACAGGAUGAGACUCUGUCUUUGAAAACAACAACAAAAAUACGUAAUGUUAAUUCCAGGUUAAUUUAUUUCUAUAAGGACACACUCACGUAGUGUAGCCUGAUCAGCAAAAUGAAAUUUGCUUUCAUUCAAAAGCCUUUAUUGAGGAAGUAUAUCUAAUCGAAUGAAAUUGUUUGUCUGCUCUUUAGAAUGAAAUUACAUGCAAUUAAAUGAGAAAAAUCUUCACUCAGUGCGUAAAACAUAGCAAGUGUAUGGAGAAUAUUGGUUCCCUUGCCUUCCUCUGCACUUGCUCUGAGUGAGCAGCUAGACUGAGGUGGCAUUAGUUUCAAGGCACAUAACUCUUGCUUUACCAACUUAUAAUUGCUCAGGAUGAAAAUAGCAACAACAUGGUACUUCCAUGCUCGGUCUUCACAUAGCCAAUGACAAGCUCCUCCAAGUCAGUUCUGAGUGUCCUUGUGGCUGAUCUGUGGACUACACCCUUGUCCCCAGGAUGUGUUAACAAACACUCUCUUCCCUCCACUUCUCUACAUCGUCAUCCCUGCUCUCCAGACGCCAGGUGUCCCAGGCUGCCUUUUCUCUCCUCUGGAUGUGGGCUGCCUGCCGGGAGCCUCUCUUAUUUUGUCACCCAGGCACUUUCAUGUUUGUUUUCUGCUCCAGCAGCCACUGGGCUGAACCCUUCACUUCCAGGGAGCUUGUUUUGUUUCACAGACUCCAGAGGAAGUAGUUCCUCCUUGAGCUCCCAGAAACAGCGUUCUCAGUGAAGUAGUUUUUCAUUUAUUGUUGUUUUGGCCCCCACAUCCCACAGUGCUGACCUCUGACUCAGGGGUUGGAGUUGUCCACUUGAAAUUUCCUUCUUCUAUUUCUCCAUUUUCUUUUGACCAAGUCUGUAAGCAUUUGCUUCUUCCCAUUACUUUCUCCAGAAGAUCUCGGCUCCUGCCACAGGAAGGUCACUGGAAAGCAGGCCUAGUAGAAUGCCAGACAGGCCUACAUACGCCUGAAUCCUUGGGAAUGCACAGCUAGGCUCUGAAAAUACCUCUGUAUGGUAUUGAAUCUACUUCUGGGGUUGAAACGGGCCUUAAAGAUACUUGGGUAGUUAAAGAAAAUUAUUUGCUCAUCUAAUCAAGUGAUGUUUGAAUCUGUCUGCUGGUGGAGUGAGGACUGUGGAGGAAGGAUCGACAAAUAUUUAUUGAGUAGAUGCUGAAUGUGACACUAUAGGCUAGGUCCUUUUCAAAGAGUUUUUUAUUUUUUCUUUGUUCCAGUAGUCUUUCAACAUAGGUUUGUUAUCCUCAUUUCACAGAUGGGAAAACUGAAGGUCAAAGAAAUUAAAGUUACUUGGUUCAUUGCACUAAGUAGCAGAGCCAGGAUUUUAAACACCUUGGCCAUGAACCCCAUACUUUUUGUACCAUAUCAAAAAAAAAGGGAGUUAGAUUCAUUAUCUAACAGGAAGUCCAUCUAUCCUGCUUGUAGAAGGACAAAAUGAUAUUGAAAGUAGGGGGCUGUGGGGCUAUUUUUUCCCCUCAAGGAAUUUUUUUUUUUUUUUUUGAGACAGAGUCUUACUCUGUUACCCAGGCUGGAGUGCAGUGGCACGGUCUUGGCUCACUGCAACCUCUGUCCCCUGAAUUCAAGCAAUUCUCCUGACUCAGCCUUCUGAGUAGCUGGGAUUACAGGUGCCCGCCACCGCGCCUGGCUAAUUUUUGGAUUUUUAGUAGAGACAGGGUUUCACCAUCUUGGCCAGGCUGGUCUUGAACUCCUGACCUCGUGAUCCACCCGCCUCGACCUCCCAAAGUGCUGGGAUUACAGGCGUGAGCCACUGCGCCCAGCCAAGGAAUAUUUUAUGAGUAAUAACUUCUCUAGAGUAUCAUUUCAACCUGGAGCCAGCCAUCUGAACAAGCCUUCCUCCAUCUCUUUUAGGAUGGUAAGCUGGGGCAUGAUGUUUAAGACUUCUUGGCUCUUUGGCAGGGCUCUGGAGGGGAAGUGAGUAAGCCAUUGGGAUGUCACUGUGGUAAUGUGGACAGGGUUUUCUGGUUUUGUCUCCUUCCCUGUGGCCUUUUUCCAUGUCCCCCCAACCCCUGGACUUCCACGGCUGGGCCAGACAUUUCCCUUCUUAGACAAAUAGACUCGCUUCAUCCCCUCCAUAGCUGCAGAGGAGAAAUCCUUGGUUUGGGUCCCAGUUUUUCCAUAUAGGCUAUUCUUGUGCUUUAUGCAGACAGAAACAUUAGUACAGUAUGUACAGAAUUAGCAGUAUAGUAAUAAGUCAUUUUAACCAACAGAUGUAAAAAAUGCUUCAGCAUACCUUUGUAAUACUAGGCCUGAUUACAGAAUGGGAGUGGUCUGUAUAAGUGAGCUGUGGUAGAAAAUACAACCCUUCAGAAUAAGUUAAAUGUAAUUAACUUCACUUUACCAGAGUCAUUUUUGUUCCCACAGUUACCCGAGUACUAAUUUCUAAACUUGAUGUGUCAAGAAUGUGGCAGAAUGGUGUCAACUUAAUGGCCAAGAAAUGUGAUCUGUUUUGAAAGAGAAUGGAAUAUUAUAGUCUAUAGUACACAAGAAUGGAAUAUUAUAGUUUAUAGUAUACUUUCUUUGAGUAACAUUUCUGUGAACAUUGAAAUUGGGAAAGAAGAUUCUGUUAUUUUCUUCUGAGACUUAAGAGAGUAUCACAUUAAAGUGGCAAAUUUGUGUUUAUGCCAAAUGUUACUGUGAUGUUUUCUUCUAUAGAAUCAAUCCCUGUAAGGUAAGUUAAAAAAACAGAAUUUCUUUCUCUAUAGCUGCGGAUGCAAAAGAACAGAGAGAUUAAAUUAACUUGCUUGUACAUAUAGAAGUUAAUGGUUGUUUCAGAUAAAGAAUGUGUAGAAUCAUAAAUUUCUUAGGACAUGGGUUAAAUGGCAGACAGAGGAAUCUUUGGGUUACAUUGUAGACAGAGGGGUGAUCUUUGCAUAUGAGCAAGUUUUGUGUCUUAUAGGUGGUGCUUUCAAGGAUGCUCCUUAGAAUCGUGAUCUCUAUUUUGAAAGGGAUGAGGAUUUGAUGUUAAUUUAAUAUUCUGUCUACUUGGCAUAUUUUGGGGUUUUGUCUGAUGUAGCAGAAAAGUUCCUACCCAGAAUAAUUUUUAAAACAUGGUAACAUUGGAUUAGGGCAGUAACACACUGCUCAUCUCAAUAAUGCUUCCGGCUUUUGAAUUCAUUAAAAUAAUAAAAGCUUUUUUUUAUCUGCCUCAUUAUUUUUAAUGCAGUUCCAUCAUAGAGCAGACUUAAUCCCUUUGUUGGUGAAGGUAGUUAAAAUUUUCCUUUUGAAAGGAAAAAAAAUUAUCACUUCUGCUAGUUAAUCUGAUACCUUUCUCUUUAGGGUAUUUUGAAACAUAUUAAUAAAGACAAAACUAAAACUAAAAUUGAGGAUCAGUCACAGCAGAGUGAGAAACAUGGCAUGGCAUUGUGGUAGAUGGAGUAGAGGCCCAGUGAUGGGGACAGGAAUCCUAAAUUCUAAGUCGAGCCCUGCUCUUCAUUAGCUAGGUGUCUCAGACAAGCAGUCACUCAACAUUUCUGCAUCUCAGUUUCUUCGUAGAGAAAAGAAGGGUUUUGAUAUAGAUCUCCAUGGUUCUUUUUAGUGCUAAUUUUUAAUCAUUUAAUUGAAAUGCAAAAAGAGGUAUUUUAAAAAUCAGGCCUUGCAUAUUUUUCAUCUCUACUGACCCCACAUCCUCCUCCAGCUACUGUCACAUUUCUAGAAUUUUCUUUCGAGAAAUGAUUCUCAAAUGAGGCGUCUACUCCUUGUCUCUAACUGCAUUGCCAAACAUAGUUUUCUGACAUCAGCUGCAUUUGUCCUGGGACCCACCCUGAGUUGUAGGGUUUUCCUGCCACUCACCUGAGAACUCCAGGCUGAGCCUUCAAGUGCACUAAGCUAAUUAAGUGCUGCAGUAACUCUGCCCUGGUGUCCUCUGAUGGCACAGUUGCAACAGAUGCAUUGUCUUCUUGCUUAUUAACAAGUAAAGGGCUGAUCCCUGGAAAAUGUUGGGGAGGGGGUUAGGAUGGCAGUUGUGCUUUUCGUUCCAGAAGUCACUUAGUCAUCUUUUCUUGGAGAUGGCCUGUAUACCUUGCCUAGCACAGUGUUUGUUGAACAGCAGGCAUGUAUGCCUAAGAGAUUUUUCUCCAUCUUUUCUUCCUCCCUCCAUUUUCCUCCAUUCUUUGCCUCCAAAUCAUAGUGUUAUGUGAUCUUCGGGGUGUCGCUUUUCUGGCCGGAAACCUCUGUGGCUGGUGGCACCUUUGCCCGUUUUUGUCCUGUGUCCAGGAAGAAUGAGGUACUCAGAGAAGUGGAAGGUGAAGAAGAUGAAGAGGAGCUUUAUUGAGUGUCAGAACAGCUCAGAGGAAGCCCACUGUGGGUAGUUCCUCUCUGUAGGCAGGUCAUCUAGUGGAGUGUUGAGCUCUCAGCAGAGAGGAGGCCCUGGAGAUGGUGGCUCCUCUUCACAAGCAGGCCGUUCAGACAUCUCUGCAGGUCUCUGAAGCUCUCAGCAGAGGGCAGCUCCUCUCUGUAGCUGGUUCGCCCAUUGUCUCCACGUGCCCUGCUCUGGCUGAGCCUGAGGCUUUUAUGGACCUCAGAGGGGAGGAAGUUCCUGCCGAUUGGCCCAUGGUCCUCCAUGUGCACCCAGACGAGGCACCACAAGUCCCCACUCCGGUCCCGGACUGGCAUCCUGGCCCCCAGCCUUCAGGCCCUCCCUGGUCUGAAGGAGGGGCCUUACGGGGACUGCCGCCUUCCACCCAGGAAUCUCUCUGCCUCCUGCUGCCCCGGGCUCGGCCCCAACCCCGGUCGGAGAUCAGAGCAGGCAUCUGGAGAGGAGAGGGGCUGGGAAGCGGGAGCAGACACCCCCGAGCCUGCAGGGAUGAAGUGGGGGGCGGGUCUUCCCGGGCCCUCCAGGGUGCAGGCUGCAGAGAUGCCAGGUCUGCACCUGCGGAGUUCACGCUCCACCAACUCAGUAAAGGUGGGGCUCCCUCUUGUCCCUGGCUCCUGCCUGCUCGAUUGAGCGCGAAGCCCAGGUCUGCAGCCGCAGCAGGGAGGCUGCAGCUCUACCCUGGAGGGCAGAUCCUGUCUGCUCCCGGCCCCCACCAAGAGCACAGGGAAGCUCCGAUCUCCAGCAUCAGUUUGGGCAGCUGUAGCCCCACCCAGGAAGGCGGGGCGCCUGCCUGCUCCAUAGAGCAGGAAGCCUGGUCUGCAGCCACGAUUUGGGUGGCUGCAGUGGCACCCACGGAGCCCCUGCCCCAACCCAGAAUGGGUGAGGCUCCCACCGCCUCCAUGGAGUGUGCAGCCCUAGCCGGCCUCCCUGUUGCAGCAGCAGCUGCCAUCAAUAGAUGGAAUUACAACCACCGAGCACGUCCUGAUUCACGUGACUUUCAACAUGUUAUAAAGGCAUACUCUUCAUGGGGGCUGUUUUCUAGCUUCUUUGUCUCACAUCAAAUGAGGGCUGCUCCCCUGGCUGGACCUAUGGCUCCUGACAUGACUCCCCGGAGGUGUGGCCUUUCUCCAGCAAUAAAUAUCGAAGCUGCUGCCGUUCCUGAAGGCGAGCCUUUCCUUGGACUGGGAAAUUAAGAGGGCAAGAUCGCCUCCCUUCCCCUAGGGUUUGCCGGGGCAGCGUUGUUUACAGUGAAAAAUGUGCCAUGCAGCCUCAGUUUUAACCUGACCAGCGAACAUAUGGACUCGGAUGGAAGCAAAAUGGUGUAUUGUAAAUACUCCGGGUGCUUCCGCCACCAACGCAAGAAGCGAGGGGGAAUCUAAUUAUUCUCGAACAGAUUGUCCUCUGCCGAACACUGUCACGCCUGCCUGCCGAUUAACAAGAAAACGGCCUGUCUCUAACUCCAAAAGCCACACACAACCGUCUGCAGGCCCCUGUGUCAGUUUGCUGCAGUGAUUGGACGACACCAUCAACCUUCACCAAGGGAGGAACAGUUUGGAGAGUUCUUGAAAUUUUCAGCUGCUGCUUUCUUUCUUCUCUUCUGCCAUCCUUCCCCUUCCUCCUCUCAGAAUUGGUGCUGUUGUGCCAAUUCUAGGUGAAUUGGAGUAUGUGGCUCUGGCUAGCAUGGGUGUGUAGGCCCCAUUAUUAGAUUCCUGGGCAGUUUGCCUCCUUUCUAGUCUCUGCUUCCCAGACUGGUUCUCCACACUCCGCUUCACUUCUAGUUUAUUCUGUCUUCCUCAAAACUCACCCCCAGGACGGUCUUCUGUUAGUCUUUUAUGCCUUACCCUGCACCGGGUCUGCAUACCCUCCAUUCUGAGAAAGCCAAUUGUGUUUACUGUCUCCUCUUUAACUGCUGAAGGAAGGAUGGGUGUUGGCACUUGGCGGAGAAGGAGGUUUGUUUGGACAGAGGUCUCUUUCCCAAACCCUUGUCGUUAACUCACAUGUGCAGGUACGUGUUCUACUGAGGUCAGGCCAUAAGCAUUUUCUUCUUUUUGGUCCAUUUACAGUUCUGUAGUUUGAUUCUUUGAUAUACAAAUGUCCUGGGUUGCUGGAAAUCCCUAGAAAUUUUAGUUUUAAGAAAAGGUCAUAAGCUGUUUUAGUACCUGGAUUCUUCUAAAAAGUUCAUGUUUAUUCACUUCCCUGUUCUUCCUGCAUGGUGCACCUUUAGGCUGGUGUAUUUUCCUUAUCGGAGAACAUGGCAUGCUUUCUUGUCUUGCCCUUUAUCUAUUUCUCCCAGAUAGGUAAGCUCCCUGAGGGCAGGGAUACCCUCUACCUUCUUGCGAUUAUAUCCUCAACAAUUGGCACUUCGAUCAGCCUGUGAAUACUCAAUAACUGUAUAUUAGAAAAUAAUGACUGAGCCUGCUUUAAGAGUGCUUUAAAAGCAUUAGGGUUGAAUAUGAGUUUUGAAGUCAGACAGACCUGGAAUAAAAUUCCUUCCUCUACUCCUUAAUAUCGGUAAGACUCUUUGACCUUUCUAAGUCUCACUUCCUCAUUUGUAUCAGAUUCGAUCUUGGAUUGUCACUAAUUCAAUAAUAGCUACUAACAUAUAUUGACCACUUAGUUUGUGCCAGGCAUUAUGCUUAGCAGUCUACAUGGAUGGUUUCAUUUAACCUUCGUGAUGUCUGUGAGAUGAAUGCUGUUUUUUUAAUUAGCUGCUUUUCUCAGGUCGGAAAGUCAAUUUAAGAGGCUUACGCUACUUACUGAAUGUUACACAGCUAGAAAGUGGGCUGAGUUCACACUCGGUCACCUGAUUGCCAAGCCUGUGCUCUUAAGAUCUCAGGUUCAUUGAAGGCAGCAACAUUUGGUGAGUAUAUAGCAGUUAAUCAAUAAUCAAAACAAGUAAAAUGUAAGAACAGCACUUUAAAACUUGUCUUUAAUCCAGUGAAGCUCAGAUGCCUAUAUUGCCUUUUAAUUGUCUAAGCACUUGCACAAAAUUAUCUAAUAUGAUCCCAACAAUUCAGUAUUAUUAGUCAAAUUUAAUAUGUAAUAAUUGGGAGAAUAAAAGCUAUUUAUUGAGCUAUUCGCUGCUGACACUACAUACAUUAUAACUAAUAUUCCUGACAGCCUUUUGAGUUAGAUGUUAUACCGCUUUCAUUUUGCAAAUAAGAACCAGAAGCUCAGAGAAGUUUCUGAACUUGAUCAAGGUCACAUUGUAGCUCAGAUUAAAAUUUGCAUCUGAGCCAGGCAUGUGUAGUCUCAGUAACUCAGGAGGCUAAAGCAGAAGGAUCCCAUGAGCCCAGGAGGUCAAGGCUAUAGUUUACUAUGAUUGAGUGUGUGAAUAGCCACUGUACUCCAGCCUGAGCAACACAGUGAGACCUUGUCUAAAGAAAGAAGAAAGACAAAUUCAGAUUUUCAAGCCUGUGUUCUUUCCACUAUACAAAACUAUUAGGAUGCUUUCGUGAGGCGGUGGGGAAGUUGACUUUCUGGAAGUUUUUUGCUAUCCAGAUCCGGGAAACCCGAUUCGUGCUUCCUGAAUUAGCUCUGUUAUAUACAUUGCAGAGUAAAUUCUGUGUCCCUAGUCUUCUGUGAAGUGGGAACAUGGUGCCUGUGUCCAAGUGUUUUAUCUCUUUCCAUUAAAGUCAGCAGUUUUCCAAAGGUCUUGUUUAUGAAGGUUAUUAGUUAUGCAAAAUGGGCCUUUAUGGAUAGUUCUAUGAAAUGAUUCCAAUUAAAAAGAAGUGGGUAGAUUGCCAGUUGGUGUCAGCUAAUUAAAUUAUGAUAUGCUCCUGUCAUUAACAAGGACUCUGACUGGAGGAAAAAUAAAAAGAUAAAAGCAAGUUUCUGAAAUUUGUUGACAGGGAGGGUAUAUUACUUUGCCCAUUCUCAUAUAAUUAGAAGAAUAAAACAGGAGCUUCCCAUUUUGUAUUUGAAAUAGGGAAAUCUGUUAUUACUUUCUUCUAGGGUAUAAUUAAUCAAGUUCAGCUGCAGUAUUUUAGAUGUUAUGGUGAAAUGGAGUUUUAUUAAAAACUGUAGUUUAAUAAUAAUGGAUCAGUUGUACUGACAUUAUUGCAAACAUAAAAAUGAGCUUCGAAUACCAAAAACACAUUCAAUAAAUUUAAUUGAGAAGGGGCUGUGUUAGAAUUUUUAGGCUGGUUCCACGUCAGUGUUUGCCAUGAGUAAGAGAAGACAUUGGUACCCAGGCUUGCCCUGAAGAGUGCCAGGGACAUGGCGGUAGCAGCAUCCCGAUCUUUAGUAGUCCUCUGGCGGGUGUAUCCGUCAGCUCUUGUCAGCUCGACAGGGAGGCUGUCCGUCCAGGUGAGGAGAGCCUUGCCGGGCUGCAGUAAGUAGCUUAUAAGUACAGUCAGGGAAUGGAGAAGAAAAUCUCCAGCUUUUCCUCCAGCUAAAGUUAUCAAUCUUUACAGGUACUUCUGGAAGCUGUUGGUUAGCCAUGCUGCUGUUGUGUGAGGAAACGAGUGCCUGGCUGGAAAGCACAAGGCUUUGGGAAAGUUACUUUUUCUGCAUUAAAUCAAAUGUUCAAUAUCUUGAUCCUGUGCCCUUCUGUGAGGUGAUGUAGUGGAGCAUUCUUCUAGACAUAUAGGUAAAUGGUGUUGACCUAACAGAUGGGAGGAUCCAGAAGCAUAGAGGCUGGGAUCCCAAAGCAUGAAUAAGCAGAAUCUAGAAUUUAGACCUUACUAAUUUGACAUUUAUGAUGAUUCAUAUAGUGCUGCUUUGAUUGAUUGAUUGAUUGAUUUGAGAUAGGGUCUCGCUCUGUUGCCCAGGCUGAAAUGCAGUGACACAAUCAUGGAUCACUGCAGCCUUGACCUCGUGGGCUCAAGUGAUCCUCCCACCUCAGCCUCCCAAGUAGCUGGGACCGUAGCCACAUGCCUCUAUAGCCGGCUGAUUUUUUGUAUUUUUAGUGGAGAUGGGAUUUUGCCACAUUGCCCCGGUUGGUCUUGAACAAGCUAUCCACCUGCCUUGGCCUCCCACAGUGCUGGGAUUACAGGUGUGAGCACCAUGCCUGUCCUGCUUUGACUUUUUUUCUUUCAAAAUGUGUUAUGGAGAGAACUGACUUAGAAUCCUAUUGUAUACCCAAGACUGCAAGGACACUGUUUAAACUUACAAAGAAAGGCACCUGUUUUGAAGCCUUUGGGAAGACGUAUUUCUUGCAGUAAUGCAUGAUUCACUAAGAGUCCCUAUCCUUUAAGCAGGUCCCAAGACCCUCUACACUGUUAGUCUAAUUGGAGGAUGCAUGUUUGUGUGUGUGUGUGUGUGUGUGUGUGUGUGUGUGUGUGUAUUAAAUAUACAACUGUAUUUCCAUUAAAAAAGAUAAUGUAAUCCAGGUUAGCUUUUUUGCCUGUUAAUUCACAUUAGUGAGAUUUUGUUGUCCAUUGUGGUGGCAAUUAUUUCUUACCAUUCCAUGUGGGUCUUACACAAUUAAGAGAGGCUGGUUGCACAGCCAGACUUGCACAGAACUUUCUACCCUCGUGUUUAUCUCCAUGAAGAAGCUGCCAAAGGUUGGAACUAAGAUCACCAAGCCCUUCUUACUUGUCUUCACACUAAACAUGCUUCAUGAUGUUCUGGCCAAUUUGUGUUUGUAGGUGUCCAGAAAAGAGCAAUAUACUUACGAGAACUCUCUACUGAAAGUACAGCAGUGCCCCCCUUAUCUGAGGUUUCAUUUUCUGUGCUUUUAGUUACCUUUGGUCAACUACAGUCUAAAAAUAUUACAUGGAAAAUUCCAGAAAUAAACAGUUCAUAGGUUUACAGUCGUGCACUGUUCUGAGAAGCAUGAUGGAAUCCCGUAUCCCCCGGGACAUGAAUCAUUCUUUCAUCAAGCGUAUCCAUGCGUAUACACGACCUACCCAUUAGUCACCUAGCAGUCACCCUCAGUUAUCAGAUGGAGUAUUGCAGUCUCACAGUGCUUGUGUUCAAGUAACCCUUAUUUGACUUAAUAAUGCUCCCAAAGUGCAAGACUAGCGCUGUCAAUUUGGAUAUGCCAAAAAGAAGCUGUAAAGUGCUUCCUUCAGUGAAAAGGUGAAAGUUCCCGACUUAAUAAGGAAAGAAAAAAAAAAUACGCUGAGGUUGCUAAGAUCUACAGGAAGAAAGAAUCUAUCCAUGAGACUGUGAAUAGUAUAUUAUUAUAAUUGUUUUAUUAGUAAUUAUUUUUGUUAAUCUCUGUGCCUAAUUUAUAAAUUAAGCUUUAUCAUAGGUAUGUAUGUAUAAGAAAAAGCAUAGAGUAUAGAGGGUACAGUACUAUCUGUGGUUUCAGGCACCCACUGAGGGUCUUGAAAUGUAUCCCCUAAGGGUAAGGGGGACUACUGAAUCGAGAAGAGAGGUAUCCUUCUGGUGCUAAAGAAAGAAAAAAGAAUGUGGUAUACUGAGGUUCAAGGCCGGUGAUGCCUGAUUCUUAGUGACUGCUAUCUUCUGAGCAAGUUCUUUUUGCUUAAAGGUAAUUUCUUAAAUGUGAGAGUAAGGAAGAGGAAAACUUUGAAAAAGAGAAUGAACCCAAACAUAAUUUGACUUCUUUAUAGGAAACUUAACUUUGUUUCAAAAUAAGUCUUUCAUUGCUUCCAGCUCGACUCUGCUUCCACUGAACAUAGAACUCAAUCACCAGGGUUUAAACAGCAACUAGUGCUGUAUUCCAGGAGAUGUGUUUACUAAAUGGAAUCUUGAAUGUUUUUACAUUGCUUUAUGAAUUCUGGACUGUUUAAUAAAUUUAAAUGAAGAUUUUUUUUAAAUGUGUUUACGUUGGCAUGUUAGUCAUUUACUGCAGAAUUUUGAGUACAUUCAGGGGGGCUGUGGUUCUGUAAAGGACUUACCACAGUUUCUAGCACACUGUACAUGUUUAAUAGACAUUAUGCUGCUGUUGCUUUUGUUGGCUACCAUAACUGUGAAGGAGAGAAUUGAGGACAGUAAAAUGAAAGUAAGUAAUCAUAGGAAUGCACCAUCUGUCAAGGUGUGCUUAAGACAUUAAAAUUCCUUUGAAUAUCCGUACAAAUGAUAAAAUUUGAGAAAUAAUUGUUUGUCUUUGUUUUACCAUUAGGCUUUUUGGUAGCUGUAUCCUGUCGCCCUGUUCAACAUUUGCUCAUAUCGUGUGGAAUUCAAAUCCUGCUAGAUCUUUUGCAGAGUUUCCAGUUCUGUUGUGUGUAUACAGUGACAGCUGAGUUCAGUAUGGGUUGUUAGAGAGAGUUGAUUUCCAAGCCAGAUACUUUUGGGUUCAAGUGACUGCUCCCUUAUGUAUUAGCUCCAUGUGACCCUAAGACAUUUAGUGUCCUAUGAACCUUUCUGAGAAUUGUUCUGAGUUUUCCUGACAGAGUCACCAGCUUCAAGAAAAACAUAGCAGUUGAACGGAUAGGUCACCUGAAUGAAGCCUGCCCACUUGGGUAGCCCCUGACAAUACCUCUACUGUCAUAAGUUAUAUAAGAUAGUAAGUAUUGAUCCUAAAGAUGGUCCUGAAUUGCCAAGGAAGAUAGACUCCACUCUGCUAAGCCAGUGACCGUGAUGUGCAUUUGAAACGCAUUUCCUUCCAGCUGGGCUUGGUGGCUCAGUUCUGUGAUCCCAGCAACUCAGGAGGCGGAGAGGGGAGGAUGGCUUAAGGCCAGGAGUUCAAGAGCAGCCUGGGCAACAUAGUGAGACUCCAUCUCUAACGGGGCAUGAUGGCAUGUGCUUAUAGUCCCUACUACUUGGGAGGCUGAGGCAGGAGGAUCACUUUAACACAAGAGUUUGAGGCUGCAGUAAGCUGUGAUUGUGCCACUGUACCCCAGCCUGGGUGACAGAUUGAGACCCCUAUCUCUAAAAAAUAAUAAAUAAAUAAAUAGCAUUUCCUUCCAAAUGGGCGGGAUAAAAAGGUUUGAUGCUUUAAAGUAUAAACUUUAAUAGGAAAAUAAUCCACCACGGAGCAGUUCCUUCAAUGAAGAUGGUGGACACUUCCGUUCUCUGUUGCACAGCUGCAGUAACUGCUAGCGGUACUAAUACUACUGGUGCUAGUACUAAUACUAAAGCUAACAUUUGUUGACCUUAUAUUGUUGCUAGAAAGUGUAAGUCUUUCAUUUUUUCUUAGUCCCAAAGAAUACGUGUACAAGAUGAAUACCACUAAUAAUUUUCCAGAGGAGGAAAUAGGCUUAGAGAAAAGUGUCUGGGCCAAAAUAAUGCACAUCCAAAGCGGUGGAGCUGGAAUUUGAAGCGAAAGGUCCUGAUCCCCAGAACCCAUCAUCCUUUUACCUGUUUUACCAAGCAUUUCAGCAGAAACCUGGCACUUGUACCUCAUUGACCAUUACUGGCAAGUCUUCUCAUUUGUAUAUAUGUGCAUUCUUCAUGAUCCUUUUGAAAGAGAUCUUGGUUUAGAUAAUAUUCUUAUGUAACUAAAGAAUGAUUUGUCCAUUCUUAUGUUUUGUCUUCGAUCAACCAAUACAUGAUGAAAAGAAUAUCUUGAUGAAAGGGAGAACUGUGUCAUUGCAGAGUGAAAUAUGGGUGAUUCAUAUCUUAAUGAAAGGGAGAGCUGUGUCAUUGUAGAGUGAAACACAGGUGAUUCAUAUCUUUGUGCGGACUAUCCAUGGCAUAUUUAAAAGCUUAGAUCAGCUGCUCUUUCCUUUCCAGCAGGAUUCUUUGCUGUCUUCUCAGAGUGUGAUGAAAUAUUCAAUUCUUUUAACAUUAGCUUGAACAAAACAAAAUUGGAGAAAUAGCCUGUCAUUAAGGCCUUCUAUAACCCACCAUUGUUAACCAUCUUGGAUUUUCUGUGUAAUAUUAGCACAUAUCAACAAUUUUUAAUUUAAAAUUCUACAUGUGUAACUAUAAAAUCAGAAUUUUUCAUUUUUGUUAAAGAAAUGUGUUUCAAACUCAGCUUCUUGAAUGCUUAUGGCAUGCAGUUUGUUUUGCUGUGAAUUGACAAAGGGAAUUACUAGAAAAAGAGAAAAAGAGUGCAGAGUUUGCUAAAUUCCUUUCCUGGAAAAUAGGGAAUUGAUAGUUGAGAAAUGAAAGUGUGUUAUAAAGCUCUUAUAACACCCACUGGAAAAUAAUCAUUAAAUAUUAGACAAUAUGAUUGGAUUAGGAAUGUUUUAGGUAGAAUGAAGUCAACCAAGUUCUGUUUUUCUGUGUGGUCUUGAGAAAAUCUAUGUAUUGAAAUACUCAUGUUAGCCUCCCAUUUUCAUUAGAUAUAUUUUAUAAACAUUUUUUGGUCCAUUGAGAAAGACCCUUUAUAACAGAAGGUUAAAAGGUUAAUUUUAGGUCUUUGGUCUAUGAACAAUUAAAAUUUCCCAGGAAGCUUAAUCAGACAUUAAUGUAACACUCAAUCAGUCCCCUGAACCUGCUGUGAGUUUCGCCAUUACUCCUUAUUGAUUAGACUGUAUUCUUUUUGCUGCUAAUGAAUUAUUUAUGGAGGAUUCCUUGAGAGUAUUCAGGCAUUGUGAAGGAAGAAGAUAAAAACCCCUUCCUCUGUAUAGCUCAGGCCAGGGGUUUGGUGGCUGCUGUGACUGAUUGUGAAGGCUCUGUCCCCUGGGUCCCUGUUGUCUUAACUGUCCUGCAGCUUUACAAAGUCUUGAGUUACUGAGAGAAGAUACAAAAGGGAUUAGAUUAUGUCUAGCAAACUUGACAGACCUGAGCAUUUAGAAAAUAUUUUCCACAUGAUUUGUUUAUAGAGAGCGGUACAAAGAAAUUUAGGUACUGUGCAAAGUAUUUAAACUUUUUUUAAAAAUAAAUUUUUGGCUGGGCGCGGUGACUCAUGCCUGUAAUCCCAGCACUUUGGGAGGCCGAGGCGGGCGGAUCACGAGGUCAGGAGAUCGAGACCAUCCUGGCUAACACGGUGAAACCCCGUCUCUACUAAAAAUACAAAAAAUUAGCCGGGCGUGGUGGCGGGAGCCUGCAGUCCCAGCUACUCGGGAGGCUGAGGCAGGAGAAUGGUGUGAACCUGGGAGGCGGAGCUUGCAGUGAGCUGAGAUCGCGCCACUGCACUCCAGCCUGGGCGACAGAGCGAGACUCCGUCUCAGAAAAAAAAUAAAUAAAUAAAUAAAUUUUUAAAAUAGUUUAUAGGAAGAGAUGAACUGACCAAAAUGCAGUCAGGUUUUUUGUUUUUUGUUUUCAGUUCGGGCUUUAUUUUGUUUUAAAUCCUAGAAGCUUAGUAUUAUGAAAACAACUGUUUUAAUGCAAAUAUCUUUCAUAAGUAGUGAGCGAAUAUAUACGAAGAGGGUGUCUUGUUCUCACAGUGCAGCACUCGGGGCGGAGUGAGGAUGGGACAGAGGAGGACUGUGCACAGCCUCGGUGCUAUGUGUAAAUUUAGUCCCUUGGCCCUAUGCACAGAAUGAGGAAAAUGAGUAAGACAUACAUACUAUAUUUUUAUUCAGCUGGAUUUAAUUAUCUUAAGGAAUAUCUUUUUAUCAUUAAAGGUAUUUUACAUUUUUAACAGAAAUAAGAAAAAAAAUUAUGUGUUUGUGUGUGUAAUGGGGGAUGACAUACAAAGCCUAAAUGAAAUUUGUUCUAAAAUUCAGGGUAAUAAUCUCUGAGAGGAAUUUGGAGAUUUCCUUUUUUUUUAAAUGUGUGCUCCCAAAUACCAAAGAGCCAUUCCAAAACUCAGUAGUAGAAUUAUAUACAAAAUGUAAUGGAAAUACCUUCUUAGAUGACUUUAAAAUGGAAAAAGAAAUCGGCUUAUCCUAUAACCCGCUACUUCCGCCCAGGGACUUGCAGAGAAACACCUGUGCGUUCUCAGAACUUGUUUCACUCUGUAGGGUGGAGGGAAAAAUCGAUCAUGAUCUAAGGCUGUGGUUGCUGAAUUGGGUUAUUAGUUGUGCACCAUCUACUUUUACCGUCUUUUGAUCUGGCCACUAUAUUUAGGUUGUUAUGGUAUCCAGUGGGGAGAAAAACAACUUAAACUUUUGCAAUUGGGAAACCAAGUGAUACUUUAAAAAACUUAAUGAACCUUGAAAAUUGCUACUCACCGUGUGAGAGUAAAAAUGUCGCAUCAGGUGGGUAGCAAAGAAAAUUGUCUUGAUACUUCCUGCAUUCUGACAAUAUUUCUUUGGCAGAUAAUCAUGUAUCUUUUACUGAGAGUCUGCUUUGUGCAGAUACCCUUAUAUUGUCCUUGUAUGCACUUUGGGGAGAUACAUAAAGGAGAAAUUAAUAUUAAGAUUAAAACAUGUGAAUCCCAUGGACUCAGGUGAGGAGAAAUGGCGAGUAACCACUAAUAGGUCCAGAGUUUCCUUAUGGAGUGAUGAAAUAUUCUGGAAUUACAUAGUGGUGAUGAGUGUACAGUUUUGCAAAUAUAUGAGAAACAACUGAAUUGUAUACUUUAGAAGCAUGAAUAUUACAGCACGUGACUUAUAUAACAAUUAAAAAAACCCAAAUCCAAAAUUCUAGUAUAUGCAUGAUCAGAAAAACAACAACCCAAUUGCUUAGCUCGUAGUCCUUGGACCUGUUGUAAGACUUCUGUUUCUUAUCCUCUGCCUACUGUUCCCUGAAUGAUCUUCCACAGUGACUGAUUUAAUAGAGUUAAAAACUUUCCGUGAACUCUCAUUGCUUUUAGUUAGGUCUGUGCAUACAGUUGGGCAGACUGUGCUCUGCAGAAGUCUAAGAAAUGUCUUUCUCAUUCUGCUUUUUUGGAUGAAUUCAGACUCAUUACAUGACAUUUAGGACUGUCUGCAUCUUAGUUCCAGCCUACCAUUCAGCAACUUCAUUCAUUUAUAUGCCCACUCAUUCACUUAUUCAUUCAUUUUAUUUGUAUGUUCAUUGGUUCCUAUGUUGGUUCAUUCAUUCAUUUACUCACUCAUUGAUUCAUUUAACUGUAUUCCUUAUCUUGCCUACUGGUUGUUAUGUUCUCCCUGCCCAGUCUGCAGAGCCCAUGCUGUACAUUGUCUCAGCCUUUUUCCCACCUUCUUCCUCCAACUCCCAGAUAUAUUCUCAAGGCCCUGCUUCUAUCCUGCAUUUUUUUGCACCUUUCUUUUGCCAUUACAGAGUUGUACUUUUUUUCUUUAAGUGCCCAGUACAUAACAAAAGAAGGUUCUAUCUCAGAUGGGGCAGCAUUAUUCACAACUGUCUCCGGGCUCCUCCAUGAGGUGUCUAAGGUGUCUACCUUUCUUUCAACUUUAAAAUCUGAACAUGAUGGACCUAUGCUUUUGGAAUUGGGGGUGGGUAGCCAACUAAAAAAUGGAGAGCCACUCUUUACCUGGAUAGCUAAUUUUUAUGUUAUUGUAGGAUAAUAACCACAAAUCAAGGCACAGCUACCUAUUAGAGCUGGCCUGAAAGCUUUAAAUUCUGCAGAAUGUGUUAUAUGUGCCAUUAACUCCAAUCUGUUGGUGCUAAUUUGAAAUGGUGGUUUGGGAACAUGUGCAGUUCCUGGUGUACUUGAAGAUUUCAGGACAUGAAUGACAAACAGUACCAAUAACUCUCUGAUCUAACAGUGAGAAGUUAUCAGCAGGCACUGCCAGAUUUGAGAAUAUUCAUCUUUUCUCACAUUGUUUUCUUUCUUAUUUUGCAUAAGUGAAUAAAGGAUGAUUUUGGAAAGCCUUACACUUGAUAUACAUUAUACAAUCCUAGAGGCCUUUAAAAAACAGGACAGAAAACUUACUUGAAUGCUUGAAAGGUAAUGGACCAGAUUAGAGUUUGAACUAGAUGACUCUUAGCAGUUCCUUCUACUUGGAUGAUGUCAUAUGCUUCUCUUUUAUUUAAAAUGUCAUUUUGGUUUGUAUAUUAAAACAAUUUUAGCUGUAUAUUUCUACUCUGUUCAUAUAUAAUAUGUAUACAUUAUGCAUAUAUAAUAUGUAUACAUUGUAUACAUACACGUAUGUGUGUGUGUGUGUGUCUGAGACAAUUGCCAGACUCAUUUUAAUUAUGAAGCUUUAAGGUGAUUGAUAUUGGGAUCACUUUUGCCUCUGCAUCUUAAGCAAAUUUAUGUUCUUUGCCUAAUGACUUCUAUAUUUGCCAGCAUGGACUUAUCUUGAGAUGACUCAGGAAUGUUACUGGAAGUGAUAGUUGUUUGGAAUAAUUUGACGCAUGUCCCUAAGAUGGCUUACUUUUGCCCCUCUGUCAUUUUAGAACAUACUUAAGCUGUGCACACUGGGAUAGCUUCCAGAAGCUUAAAUUUUAGGAUUUAAUUAGGUCAUACAAUAUUAAUUAAUAAAAAACUUUUUGAAUUGCUUUGUGUUCGCAGGUACUGUGUCUGAUGCUCCACAUAGAAGGAUGAAUGGGACCAAAGGUCCUACUCUAAACCAUUCACAGAGGAGUAGUGAGACCUAUUAGAAAGGAUUUGAAACAAAAGCUUUCAGGUGAUCUGCAACUCUUUCACCAUCUGUAAUGCGGAGAUGCAGGAAGUUGGUGUUGGCCUAUAUCCCAGUAUCUCUUUGCUCAAUCACAGCUGUGACCCCAACUGUUCGAUUGUGUUCAAUGGGCCCCACCUCUUACUGCGAGCAGUCCGAGACAUCGAGGUGGGAGAGGAGCUCACCAUCUGCUACCUGGAUAUGCUGAUGACCAGUGAGGAGCGCCGGAAGCAGCUGAGGGACCAGUACUGCUUUGAAUGUGACUGUUUCCGUUGCCAAACCCAGGACAAGGAUGCUGAUAUGCUAACUGGUGAUGAGCAAGUAUGGAAGGAAGUUCAAGAAUCCCUGAAAAAAAUUGAAGAACUGAAGGCACACUGGAAGUGGGAGCAGGUUCUGGCCAUGUGCCAGGCAAUCAUAAGCAGCAAUUCUGAACGGCUUCCCGAUAUCAACAUCUACCAGCUGAAGGUGCUCGACUGCGCCAUGGAUGCCUGCAUCAACCUCGGCCUGUUGGAGGAAGCCUUGUUCUAUGGUACUCGGACCAUGGAGCCAUACAGGAUUUUUUUCCCAGGAAGCCAUCCCGUCAGAGGGGUUCAAGUGAUGAAAGUUGGCAAACUGCAGCUACAUCAAGGCAUGUUUCCCCAAGCAAUGAAGAAUCUGAGACUGGCUUUUGAUAUUAUGAGAGUGACACAUGGCAGAGAACACAGCCUGAUUGAAGAUUUGAUUCUACUUUUAGAAGAAUGCGACGCCAACAUCAGAGCAUCCUAAGGGAACGCAGUCAGAGGGAAAUACGGCGUGUGUCUUUGUUGAAUGCCUUAUUGAGGUCACACACUCUAUGCUUUGUUAGCUGUGUGAACCUCUCCUAUUGGAAAUUCUGUUCCGUGUUUGUGUAGGUAAAUAAAGGCAGACAUGGUUUGCAAACCACAAGAAUCAUUAGUUGUAGAGAAGCACGAUUAUAAUAAAUUCAAAACAUUUGGUUGAGGA